GGUGCGCCGUGGCGCCGCCUGCGACCGGCAGCUCGUUCGCCGCACUUUGGAGGCUUCGGCUGCCCCUCCGACCCACGUAGGGCCCGGACCCGGGCCUCCUUGUGAACAGCGUGCCGGCUUCGCCCCACGGGUUCACCGGCUGGCUGGGCUUCAAGCGCCGAGGCCGCCGCAGUGACCCCGCCCCCGGGCCGAGGAUGUGAGGCGGGCCGGGCGUCCCCACACCGGGCCCGGGCGCCGGGAGUGGGCGUCUGGGCAGCGCCAGGCGAUGGCCCUGCUGCUGGUGCUCCUCGCCUCUUGGGGCCUGGGGCAGUGAGGGGGCCGGCGGGCGUGGGCCGAGUGGCCGCGGGCGCCAUGGAGGGGGUGCUGUACAAGUGGACCAACUAUCUGAGCGGUUGGCAGCCUCGAUGGUUCCUUCUCUGUGGGGGAAUAUUGUCCUAUUAUGAUUCUCCUGAAGAUGCCUGGAAAGGUUGCAAAGGGAGCAUACAAAUGGCAGUCUGUGAAAUUCAAGUUCAUUCUGUAGAUAAUACACGCAUGGACCUGAUAAUCCCUGGGGAACAGUAUUUCUACCUGAAGGCCAGAAGUGUGGCUGAAAGACAGCGGUGGCUGGUGGCCCUGGGAUCAGCCAAGGCUUGCCUGACUGACAGUAGGACCCAGAAGGAGAAAGAGUUUGCUGAAAACACUGAAAACUUGAAAACCAAAAUGUCAGAACUAAGACUCUACUGUGACCUCCUUGUUCAGCAAGUAGAUAAAACAAAAGAAGUGACCACAACUGGUGUGUCCAAUUCUGAGGAGGGAAUUGAUGUGGGAACUUUGCUGAAAUCAACCUGUAAUACUUUUCUGAAGACCUUGGAAGAAUGCAUGCAGAUCGCAAAUGCAGCCUUCACCUCUGAGCUGCUCUACCGCACUCCACCAGGAUCACCUCAGCUGGCCAUGCUCAAGUCCAGCAAGAUGAAACAUCCUAUUAUACCAAUUCAUAAUUCAUUGGAAAGGCAAAUGGAGUUGAGCACUUGUGAAAAUGGAUCUUUAAAUAUGGAAAUAAAUGGUGAGGAAGAAAUCCUAAUGAAAAAUAAGAAUUCCUUAUAUUUGAAAUCUGCAGAGAUAGACUGCAGCAUAUCAAGUGAGGAAAAUACAGAUGAUAAUAUAACAGUCCAAGGUGAAAUAAGGAAGGAAGAUGGAAUGGAAAACCUGAAAAAUCAUGACAAUAACUUGACUCAGUCUGGAUCAGACUCAAGUUGCUCUCCGGAAUGCCUCUGGGAGGAAGGCAAAGAAGUUAUCCCAACUUUCUUUAGUACCAUGAACACAAGCUUUAGUGACAUUGAACUUCUGGAAGACAGUGGCAUUCCCACAGAAGCAUUCUUGGCAUCAUGUUAUGCUGUGGUUCCAGUAUUAGACAAACUUGGCCCUACAGUGUUUGCUCCUGUUAAGAUGGAUCUUGUUGGAAAUAUUAAGAAAGUAAAUCAGAAGUAUAUAACCAACAAAGAAGAGUUUACCACUCUCCAGAAGAUAGUGCUGCACGAAGUGGAGGCGGAUGUAGCCCAGGUUAGGAACUCAGCGACUGAAGCCCUCUUGUGGCUGAAGAGAGGUCUCAAAUUUUUGAAGGGAUUUUUGACAGAAGUGAAAAAUGGGGAGAAGGAUAUCCAGACAGCCCUAAAUAAUGCAUAUGGUAAAACAUUGCGGCAACACCAUGGCUGGGUAGUUCGAGGGGUUUUUGCGGAAAUCCAACAGAAAACACUUGACACCAAAACAUACCCUGAUGAAGAUCCUGAACUUCAAGAAUGAAGAAAGAAUUCCUCACCAUUCAGGCAGAAAAAGCAAGUCACCAAGGGACCUCAAACUUCCUUUCCACAAGAUUCUGUGACGGGAAACAAUGGGGGAGUAUUUCCGAAGUUCUGAGUAGGAAAAAAGAAUGACUCAAAUGUAUUAUUGCCAACCAAGUCGUCAAAUCUAAUGUCAAGUUCUCUUAAGCAGGUAAGAACUCAGAACAUAAUACCUGAGUGCCUUCUUAAGGAAACCAUUUGAUAGGAAAGAUGAACCAAAUAACUCAAUGAUGGAUGAGCUGGUAGAAAAAAAGCUGGUGGUGAACCAAGGUCAAACUGGAAAUUAUAGUCACAGUAUAGAUAUAGAUUAUAAAUAUUACAAACCCUAAGAUAGCUAAUAAAUUGGGAAUGGGAGAAGGGAGGAUAUAAGAGCACUAAUGCCCUCUUAUUUUCAUAGCAGAGACUUGAUACUGUCUCAACUUUUUUCAAAAACACAAUUUCUUAAAUUUUUUGGUAAUCUUUUAAAUAAACAGAUUUCUAAAAAGAAAUACGUAUUGUUUCAGUUCACUUUAGUUUCUUGUCUUAAAUACGAGCCAAUUAGCUGAAUGCUAUUUAUUUAAAAAUAAAUAUGAUAAGAAAUAAAUUAAAAAUAAAUAUGAUUUUACGUUUAUAAAAAUUCCUCAGCCCGGCAUGGUGGCUCACACCUGUAAUCCCAGUGCUUUGGGAGGCCAAGGCAGGAGGAUCGCUUGAGCCAAGGAGUUUGAGACCAGCUUGGGCAACAGAGCAAGACCCCUUCUCUACAAAAAAAUCUUUAAAAAUUAGCCAGGCGUGAUGGUGCAUGCCUGUAGUUCCAACUACUCAGGAGAGUGAGGUGGGAAGAUCGCUUGAGCCCAGGAGUUCAAGGCUGCAGGCCACUGCCCUCCAGUCCGGGCAAUACAGCAAGACCCUAUCUCUAAAUAUAUAUUUCCUCUAUCUCUCUAUCUCUGUAGAGACAAAUCAAGAAUUAUAUUCACCUAAAGUGGAUUACGAUUAUUUUUAGGUGGGUAUUGAUUUUGUUUUACUCUUUUUUUUUUUUGUACUUUACUAUAUUGCUUGACUUUUGUUUGAUGCCUAUGAUAUCUUUUUAUUUUUUAAUGGAGGAUGGGAGGUGUUUUUCUAAAAACAAGGUUAAAAAUCAUUGUAGAGUGUGGUGGACCCCCGGCAGGUGCUGCUCCUUAUAAUGACAUUUGCUUCAUAACUCCUAUCAAGGUUCUUUAAAAUUUCUAGCUUUAUCUCACUACAUUUUUUUUUCGCUGCUAAUUUUUCUCAUAAGCUGCUAUUCCUUUACCCACACGAAGCUAUUGCUCAUCCAAACAUUCCAUUUUAUACAACUCAUUAAGGAUUGGGACAUUCUUUUGGGGCUAAAGGGAAAGACUGAAUGCCAGUAUGAUACCUAGGGACUUGCCCAGUACAUCUGAAAUAAAUGGAAAAUUAGGGAAAAAAAGCCAUUUGGAGUGGUUGACAGUCAUCUUACAAGAAGCCAGAAAGACUCUUAGCAACAUGGGGAUUUUGCACAUGAAUUGGCUGCAGUUCACCGAAGGAGCUGAAAGAUUUCUUUCUUUGUGCUUCUGUGAGUUUGGAAAUGAAAUGUCAAUCCUUUCUCUGCCCAAGUGAAAUUGCUGGGCCAUAGAGCAUUAGUUCAGCAUUAGCUUAUGCUGAUCAAACCCAGCCAUCCAGAGAUGGCAGAUGAGAGAAUGGAGCAGUAAACUUUAUUCCACACACGUUUGUUUUAAGGACCAUUCAGCCUUAUGUUCAUAGAAGCCCGUGGAAGCCCUGUAUUCUCUUGUGGCAUGUAUGUGAGCAACUAAGGACCCUGUCUCUGUGUGUUACACAAGACUUUUAUAAAAUCCCAAAUCCUCAACUUGAUUUGUAUGAAAAGAUGAUCACAGGAUUGUGGAGCUGGAAGACUCCUUCGUUCAUAGUGGGAGUCAUAGUAACUAUUGCAAAAGAUUGUUAUAAGGAUCAAGUCGGGAAUUGUGCACAGUGUCUAGCACCAGGCAAGAGCUACAAAAACGGUGGUGGUAAUAAUAGUCGUUGUUAUUGUUUGAAAGGGAAGUAUGGCUCCAUCCUGCCUGGAGUUUACCUGGUGGAAUAAGCCUUUUCUUAUUUGUUCCACUUGUCCCUGCCCUCACAGAAGAUUCACUGCUGCCCCUAGUCUCCCCACUUUGCACUGUGUGUCACGGCACCUUCAAGUAGAAGACCCUCAUCUAGUCAUGUCUGUAUGUGAAUGUGGCACUACCAUUUCCUUGCCUGAGCCCCGGAGCCAGCUGCAGUGCUCCACAGCUGUAUCCCAGUUGGAGGAUUCCAGAAGAAUGGCUGAGCAUUAGGAUGCACCUGACACUCUCCAUAGGACCCCAUUCUCCAUACUCCGGAGGACAUCUGUUUUUCUGCCUUCAUCUCCUCCCCUUAUUCGGAGCACACUCUUAUUCCUUUGAAUGAACUGCCUUCUCCACUCUGAGCUCUGGUUGGGCCGCCGGUCACAGUCCCCAGGCCUCUGGCCACAGCGUGGGCAUAUGAUCCAGAAUAGGCCCAUCAUGGGACUUCCCUGGGACUAUGUAUUUAGAGACUGGGAGAGACGAUCCCUUUCCCCUAGGGUUAAAGUGAGAUCGAGAGAAAGUGAGGAUAGAGAUACGACAUUUAGUCCUGAAUCAAGUCAUGCCUGGGGCCACCUCCAUGCUUGCUUUUUCUGGUUAUGUAAGUCAGUAAGUCCCACUUUAUUUAAAGUUCAUUGGAAUUAGGAUUCUAUCACUUGAAACCAAAAGAAGCCUGAUAAGUUUUCAAAUAAGUCCAAGAUAUGCCUUUGGUGAGGUUACCAGAUUUUCUCUCAAUGCUUUCCUCCUCUGCAUAACAUAUGGGCACGUUAUUUUACAGUGGGGUUAACAGAAGAAAAUUGAGAAACAUGCCUAAACUGGGGCCAACUGGGGUCCAAUUUCAGUUAUAACUAUUUGGUCUGCUGCAGCAUCAGGACACUGGCUGUUAGCUUUUACUUCUUUCCUAAAUAACAAUAAUAAUUAUGAAUACUUAUGAACUACCAACCACUGUGUGAAAAACUUCCUAUAGGUUCUCACUUAACCCUGAGAGUAGCUGUGAAGUGGACACUAUUAUUAACCCCAUUUAUAGGUGAGAAGAGGAAAUGUUGCUUGUCUUGCUCAAGGUGGGUGAGAAAGCACAUGAGUGGUAGGACUGUGAGCCCAGACAGCCUGCCUCUAAGCCCACAGCCUUACCACUAUGUGGCUAUGUCCUGUGAUGUAAGACAGAGCGGAGGCUGGAAUCAGACCACGGGUCAAAUCCCAGCACUGCCACACCCUCACCAUGGGAUUUUGAGCAUGUUAGUUAACAUCUCUGGAUUCCCUUUCUCCUCUGUAAACUGAGAUAAAGAGAUUGCACAACCCUGCUCAUAAGAUUCUUGCAAGGACUAAAUGAGGCAGGGGAUGUAAAUCGCCUGGCAUGUUGCCUUACUCUCCUGGACAGGCAAAAGCUUGGUGUUUCCAUCAUGACCCACUUCUGAGUCUCCUAAGCUCAGCUGCCUGCCGCAUGCAUGGGUACUCAGCUCCAAGCAGCUCCUCUGCUUCCUUCUCAUCUUCCUGGGUGUGAGCAUGGAAACCACGUUGGACUUGGAAUGGUCAGAUUGGACUCUGGUCUGCCUUUCAGUUUACAAACUGGGUCACCUUGGACAAAUCCUUUAACCCCUUGAUCUUUUGUUUCCUAGUCAGUGAGACUGAGAUGGUGUUGUUAUGAGGAUUAGCUGAGAUGACACAUUGCUAGCAUAUAGCACUGUGCCUGGCACAUGGCUAGUACUAGUUAAGUUAUGAUGGAAUGGUUAGGGGACAUAUGUACCUGUUUCUGACAGAUAGCUAAUUCCUUUUCAGCUCACUCUAACUGUACCUAGACACAAAGGAAAUUACAUUAUCCGAAGGGACAUCUUUAGACUGUUCAUAAAUGUCAUCACUCAUACUUAAUGUCUUUUUCUUUUAAGUUCCAUUUAGUUCUUUGAUUUAAUCUGCUAAAUAUUAGGGAUUGGUAGGAGAGCAAGUUUCUACUUUUUUUUUUUUUUUCCAGACAGAGUCUUGCUCUUGUUGCCCAGGCUGGAGUGUAGUGGCGCAAUCUCGGCUCACUGCAACCUCCACCUCUUGGGUUCAAGCAAUUCUUCUGCCUCAGCCUCCUGAGUAGCUAGGAUUAUAGGCGCCUGCCACCACGCCCAGCUAAUUUUUUGUAUUUUUAAUACAGCCAGGGUUUCAUCACAUUGGCCAGGCUGGUCUCGAACUCCUUUUUUUUUUAAAUUUUAUUAUUAUUAUACUUCAAGUUUUAGGAAACAUGGGCACAACUUGCAGGUUUGUUACAUAUGUAUACAUGUGCCAUGUUGGUGUGCUGCACCCAUUAACUCAUUUAGCAUUAGGUCAUUUAGCAUUAGGUAUAUCUCCUAAUGCUAUACCUCCCCCCUCCCCCCACCCCACAACAGGCCCCAGUGUGUGAUGUUCCCCUUCCUGUGUCCAUGUGUUCUCAUUGUUCAAUUCCCACCUAUAAGUGAGAACAUGAGGUGUUUGGUUUUUUGUCCUCGUGAUAAUUUGCUGAGAAUGGUGGUUUCCAGCUUCAUCCACGUCCCUACAAAGUACAUGAAUUCAUCAUUUUUUAUGGCUGCAUAGUAUUCCAUGGUGUAUAUGUGCCACAUUUUCUUAAUCCAGUCUAUCAUUGUUGGACAUUUGGGUUGGUUCCAAGUCUUUGCUAUUGUGAAUAGCGCUACAAUAAACAUACGUGUGCAUGUGUCUUUAUAGCAGCAUGAUUUAUAAUCCUUUGGGUAUAUACUCAGUAAUGGGAUGGCUGGGUCAAAUGGUAUUUCUAGUUCUAGAUCCCUGAGGAAUCACCACACUGACUUCCACAAUGGUUGAACUAGUUUACAGUCCCACCAACAGUGUAAAAGUGUUCCAUUUCUCCACAUCCUCUCCAGCACCUGUUGUUUCCUGACUUUUUAAAGAUCGCCAUGCUAACUGGUGUGAGAUGGUAUCUCAUUGUGGUUUUGAUUUGCAUUUCUCUGAUGGCCAGUGAUGAUGAGCAUUUUUUCAUGUGUUUUUUGGCUACAUAAAUGUCUUCUUUUGGGAAGUGUCUGUUCAUAUCCUUCACCCACUUUUUAAUGGGGUUGUUUGUUUUUUUCUUGUAAAUUUGUUUGAGUUCAUUGUAGAUUCUGGAUAUUAGCCCUUUAUCAGAUGAGUAGGUUGCAAAAAUUUUCUCCCAUUCUGUAGGUUGCCUGUUCACUCUGAUGGUAGUUUCUUUGCUGCGCAGAAGCUCUUUAGUUUAAUUAGAUCCCAUUUGUCAAUUUUGGCUUUUGUUGCCAUUGCUUUUGGUGUUUUAGACAUGAAGUCAUGGCCCAUGCCUAUGUCCUGAAUGGUAUUGCCUAGGUUUUCUUCUAGGGUUUUUAUGGUUUUAGGUCUAACAUGUAAAUCUUUAAUCCAUCUUGAAUUAAUUUUUGUAUAAGGUGUAAGGAAGGGAUCCAGUUUCAGCUUUCUACAUAUGGCUAGCCAGUUUUCCCAGCACCAUUUAUUAAAUAGGGAAUCGUUUCCCCAUUUCUUGUUUUUGUCAGGUUUGUCAAAGAUCAUAUAGUUGUAGAUAUGUGGCAUUAUUUCUGAGGGCUCUGUACUGUUUCAUUGAUCUAUAUCUCUGUUUUGGUACCAGUACCAUGCUGUUUUGGUUACUGUAGCCUUGUAGUAUAGUUUGAAGUCAGGUAGCGUGAUGCCUCCAGCUUUGUUUUUUUGGCUUAGGAUUGACUUGGCAAUGCGGGCUCUUUUUUGGUUCCAUGUGAAGUCUAAAGUAGUUUUUUCCAAUUUUGUGAAGAAAGUCAUUGGUAGCUUGAUGGGGAUGGCAUUUAAUCUAUAAAUUACCUUGGGCAGUAUGGCCAUUUUCACGAUAUUGAUUCUUCCUACCCAUGAGCAUGGAAUGUUCUUCCAUUCGUUUGUAUCCUCUUUUAUUUCCUUGAGCAGUGGUUUGUGGUUCUCCUUGAAGAGGUCCUUCACAUCCCUUGUAAGUUGGAUUCCUAGGUAUUUUAUUCUCUUUGAAGCAAUUGUGAAUGGGAGUUCACCAUGAUUUGGCUCUCUGUUUGUCUGUUAUUGAUGUAUAAGAAUGCUUGGGAUUUUUGCACAUUGAUUUUGUAUCCUGAGACUUUGCUGAAGUUGCUUAUCAGCUUAAGGAGAUUUUGGGCUGAGACGAUGGGGUUUUCUAGAUAUACAAUCAUGUCAUCUGCAAACAGGGACAAUUUGACUUCCUCUUUUCCUAAUUGAAUGCCCUUUAUUUCCUUCUCCUGCCUGAUUGCCCUGGCCAGAACUUCCAACACUACGUUGAAUAGGAGUGGUGAGAGAGGGCAUCUUUGUCUCUUUUGAUCUUUGUUGGUUUAAAGUCUGUUUUAUCUGAGACUAGGAUUGCAACCCCUGCCUUUUUUUGUUUUCCAUUUGCUUGGUAGAUCUUCCUCCAUCCCUUUAUUUUGAGCCUGUGUGUCUCUGCAUGUGAGAUGGGUUUCCUGAAUACAGCACACUGAUGGGUCUUGACUCUUUAUCCAAUUUACCAGUCUGUGUCUUUUAAUUGGAGCAUUUAGCCCAUUUACACUUAAGGUCAAUAUUGUUAUGUGUGAAUUUGAUCCUGUCAUUAUGAUGUUAGCUGGUUAUUUUGCUCGUUAGUUGAUGCAGUUUCUUCCUAGCCUUAAUGGUCUUUACAGUUUGGCAUGUUGGUACCGGUGGCUGGUACCAGUUGUUCCUUUCCAUGUUUAGUGCUUCCUUCAGGAGCUCUUUUAGGGCAGGCCUGGUGGUGACAAAAUCUCUCAGCAUUUGCUUGUCUGUAAAGUAUUUUAUUUCUCCUUCACUUAUGAAUCUUAGUUUGGCUGGAUAUGAAAUUCUGGGUUGAAAAUUCUUUUCUUUAAGAAUGUUGAAUAUCGGCCCCCACUCUCUUCUGGCUUGUAGAGUUACUGCCGAGAGAUCAGCUGUUAGUCUGAUGAACUUCCCUUUGUGGGUAUCCCGAUCUUUCUCUCUGGCUGCCCUUAACAUUUUUUCCUUCAUUUCAACUUUGGUGAAUCUGAUAAUUAUGUGUCUUGGAAUUGCUCUUCUUGAGGAGUCUCUUUGUGGCGUUCUCUGUAUUUCCUGAAUUUGAAUGUUGGCCUGCCUUGCUAGAUUGGGGAAGUUCUCCUAGAUAAUAUCCUGCAGAGUGUUUUCCAGCUUGGUUCCAUUCUCCCCAUCACUUUCAGGUACACCAAUCAGACGUAGAUUUGGUCUUUUUACAUAGUCCCAUAUUUCUUGGAGGCUUUGUUCGUUUCUUUUUAUUCUUUUUUCUCUAACCUUCUCUUCUCGCUUCAUUUCAUUCAUUUCGUCUUCCAUUGCUGAUACCCUUUCUUCCAGUUGAUCACGUUGGCUACUGAGGCUUGUGCAUUCGUCACAUAGUUCUCGUGCCGUGGUUUUCAGCUCCAUCAGGUCCUUUAAGGACUUCUCUGCAUUGAUUAUUCUAGUUAGCCGUUUGUCUAAUUUUUUUGCAAGGUUUUAACUUCUUUGCCAUUGGUUCGAACUUCUUCCUUUAGCUUGGAGUAGUUUGAUCUUCUGAAGCAUUCUUCUCUCAACUCGUCAAAGUCAUUCUCUGUCCAGCUUUGUUCCGUUGCUGGUGAGGAGCUGCGUUCCUUUGGAGGAGGAGAGGCGCUCUGACUUUUAGAGUUUCUGGUUUUUCUGCUCUGUUUUUUCCCCAUCUUUGUGGUUUUAUCUACCUUUGGUCUUUGAUGAUGGUGACGUACAGAUGGAUUUUUGGUGUGGAUGUCCUUUCUGUUUGUUAGUUUUCCUUCUAACAGUCAGGACCCUCAGCUGCAGGUCUGUUGGAGUUUGCUGGAGGUCCACUCCAGACCCUGUUUGCCUGGGUAUCAGCAGCGGUGGCUGCAGAACUGCAGAUAUUGGUGAACCGCAAACGCUGCUGCCUGAUCGUUCCUCUGGAAGUUUUGUCUCAGAGGAGUACCCGGCCAUGUGAGGUGUCAGUCUGCCCCUACUGGGGAGUGCCUCCCAGUUAGGCUACUCGGGGGUCAGGGACCCACUUGAGGAGGCAGUCUGCCUGUUCUCAGAUCUCCAGCUGCGUGCUGGGAGAACCACUACUCUCUUCAAAGCUGUCAGACAGGGACAUUUAAGUCUGCAGAGGUUACUGCUGCCUUUUGUUUGUCUGUGCCCUGCCCCCAGAGGUGGAGCCUACAGAGGCAGGCAGGCCUCCUUGAGCUGUGGUGGGCUCCACCCAGUUCGAGCUUCCCGGCUGCUUUGUUUACCUAAUCAAACAACUAACUCGGCAAUGGCAGGUGCCCGUCCCCCAGCCUCGCUGCCGCCUUGCAGUUUGAUCUCAGACUGCUGUGCUAGCAAUGAGCGAGGCUCCGUGGGCGUAGGACCCUCCAAGCCAGGUGCGGGAUAUAAUCUCCUGUUGUGCCGUUUGUUAAACCCGUUGGAAAAGCGCAGUAUUAGGGUGGGAGUGACCCGAUUUUCCAGGUGCCAUCUGUCACCCCUUUCUUUGACUAGGAAAGGGAAUUCCUUGACCCUUGCGCUUCCUGGGUGAUGCGAUGUUGCGCCCUGCUUUGGCUCACGCAUGGUGCGCUGCACCCACUGUCCGGCACUCCCCAGUGAGAUAAACCCGGUACCUCAGUUGGAAAUGCAGAAAUCACCCGUCUUCUGCGUCGCUCACGCUGGGAGCUGUAGACUGGAGCUGUUCCUAUUCGGCCAUCUUGGCUCCACCUCAACCUGGUCUCGAACUCCUGACCUCAGGUGAUCCACCUGCCUCAGCCUCCCAAAGUUCUGGGAUUACAGGUGUGAGCCACCGUGCCCAGCCUUUUCUUUCUUUUUACAAUUUCUUACAAGUUUUUAUUUUUAUAAAGUACUUAAAUAUCUCAAAUUUCAGAAAACAAGAUAUUUAAUCACACAUCCAAACAGAGAAUUCUCUAAUAUAGCCCCUUAUCAAUUCCCUGCAUUGUAAGACAGUUCUUUCAGUAGAAGUGUCUCCACACCAAGCAAGAAACAAAACACCACAAACAAUGAAUACCUGCGGUAUCCAAGUCACCAAUUAGAUGCCUUGCAGACCCAGAAAUACAUCAGAAACACUCUGCUCUCCAGGAAUGUGCAGUGUAGUAAUGGACAUAAGACAUACUCUUGAAAAACUAUGCUAUAAAACAGAAUGUAAUGCAGGUUCUCUAAGAAGUAUAAACAAAUGCAUUAGGAACCCAGAGUGCGGAGUAUGUCCUUGUAGGUGAAGGCGAGGCACAAAGUCUCCCUUGAGGUGGCAGUGAAGUUCAUGUAUAAUGAAUGUUGUGUUCCUUGGCACUCUUUUGGCUGCAAAUGACCAAAGACCUAAGUAAUGCUGUUAACCAGCUCAGCCUCAUCGACUUUUGUAGAGCACUACAUCCAGGGAGAAUACACAUUCUUUUCAAGUACAUGUGGAAUAUACACCAAGUUAUACCAUAUGCUGGACCGUAAAACAAAUUUAUAAUCAUUGAUCCAAAGAGGAAUUCUGGGAAAUGGAGAGUGGCAGCAGGAUAAUUCUUCACUCUCUCUGAAUUCCCACAUGAAAUAGAACAACUAGAUAACAUAACAAAAAAUUCAUGAACAGCUUGUAUAACAAAGCUAGUUAUUCAUUUCCUAAGGGAAUAGCAAAUCACCACCAACCAGGUCGCUUAAAACAACAGAAAUGUAUCCUCUCAUAGUUCUGGAGACUGGAAGUCCAAAACUAAGGUGUUGGCAAGUCCAUCUCCCUCUGAAGGCUUUAGGGAGGGAUCCUUCCUUACCUCUUCCUAGCUUCCGGUGGUUGUCGGCAAUCCUAGCAUUCUUUGGCUGUAGCAGCAUCACUCCAAUCUCUGCCUCUAUCUUUAUGUGUCUGUUGUCUUCAUGUGUCUCCAAAUCUCUCUCUCCUCAUAAGGAGACCUGUCAUUGGAUUUAGAGCCCACUCUAAUUCAGUAUGACCCCAUCUUGACUAUAUCCGUAAAGAUCCUAUUUCCAAAUAAGGUCACAUUCACAGGUACCAGAGAUUAGGAUUUAAAUAUAUCUUUUGGGACUAGGCACGGUGGCUCACACCUGUAAUCCCAGUACUUUGGGAGGCCAAGGAGGGUGGAUCACUUGAGGCCAGGAGUUCAAGACCAGCCUGGCCAACAUGGUGAAACCCUGUCUCUACUAAAAUUACAAAAAAUUAGCCAGGUAUGGUGGUGUACACCUGUGGUCCCAGCUACUCAGGAAGCCGAGGCAAGAGAAUCACUUGAACCUAGGAGGUGGAGGUUGCAGGGAGCAAGAUCACACCACUGCACUCCAACCUGGGCAACAGAGCGAGACUGUGUCUCAAAAAAAUUAAUUAAUUAAUUAAUUAAAUAAAUCUUAUAGAGGAACACAAUUCAAAUAAUAACACUAGAUAUCAUUACACCUAAGAAUAUGAUAAUAUUGUCUCCCCAAGAUUAAGGAACAAGGUAAGGAUAUCUGUUGUCACCAUAACCACUUCUAUUCAUUAUUGAAGUUGAGGUCAUAGCCAGAGCAGUAACUCAAGAAAAGACAAUAAAAGGUAUACAGAUUGAAAAGGAAGAAAUAAAAACUACUUGCAAAUGAUGUAUACAAAUAAACCUGAGGAUUCUGCAAAGACUAUUUAAGCUAAUAGCUAAAUGUAGGAUGUUUGCAAGAUGGAUCAAUGUAGAAAAGUAAAUUGCAGCUGGGCAUGGUGGCUCAUGCCUGUAAUCCAAACACUUUAGGAGGCCAGGGUGGGCAGAUCACCUGAGGUCAGGAGUUCAACACCAGCCUGGCCAACAUGGUGAAACCCCGUCUCUACUAAAAAUACAAAAAUUAGCUGGGUGUGGUGGUACACACCUGUAGUCACAGCUACUCGGGAGGCUAAGGCAGAAGAAUGGCUUGAACCUGGGAGGCAGAGAUUGCAGUGAGCCGAGAUUGCACUCCAGCCUGGGCAACAGAGUGAGACUUGGGGGAAAAAAAAAAAAGAAGAAAGAAAGAAAAGAAAAGUAAAUGCAUUUCUACAUACCAACAAAAACAAUUAGAAAAUGAAAUUUGAAAGACAAUGCUGUUUAAGACAGAAUAAAAGUCUGUUUUAGUCUGUUGAGGCUGCUGUAAUAAAAUACCAUAGACCGGGUAGCUUAUGAACAACGGGAGUUUAUUUCUCACAGUUGUGGUGGCUGGGAAGUCUGAGAUCGUGGUGCCAGCAUGGUGCCAGAAACCGUGGUCGGGUUCUGGUGAGGGCUCUCUUCCAGGUUGCAGACAGCCACCUUCUUGCUGUGUCCUCACAUGGAGGAAGGAGCAAACAAGCUCUCAGGGGCCUCUUUUAUAAGCACAGCAGUCCCAUUCAUGAGAGUCCUGCCUUCAUGAUCUAAGCACCUCCCAAAGGCCCCACCUCCUGAUACCAUCACCUUAGGCGCUAGGAUUUCAACAUAUGAAUUUGGGGAGAACACAGAGAUUCAGACCAUAGCAAAAUUUGUAAUCAGGGGAAAAUUUAAUAAAAUAUGUGCAAAAUCUUUACACACUGAAAACUAUAAAAACAUUCUGCGACAAGUUAGAGAAGACCUAAAGAAAAGAGCUAUACCACAUUCAUGGGUUAAAAGAUCUGAUAUUGGUAAGAUGUCAGUUCUCAAAUAGAUCUCAAGGUUCAGUGCAAUCCCAAUCUAAAUACCAGCAGGUAGAUAUGACACUAAAAGCAUGAACAACAAAAGAAAAUAAAUAAAUAAAUUGUACUUUAUCAAAUUAAAAAACUUUUGUGCAUCAAAGGACAUUGUCAAAGAAAUGAGAAGAUAACCUACAGAAUGAGAGAAAGUAUUUGCAAAUCAUACAUCUGAUAAGGGACUGGUAUCUAGAAUCUACAAAGAAUUCUUAUAACUCAGCAACAGGAAAACAAACAACCCAAUUUAAAAAUAGGCAAAGGACUUGAAUAGACAUUUCUCUAAAGAAGACAUACAGAUGGCCAAUAAGCACAUGAAAAGGUGCUCAACAUAGUAGGGAAAUACAAAUUAGAACAACAAGGAGAUACCAUUUCAUACCUACCAGCAUGGCUAUAAUAGUAAUUUUUAAAAUGCAGAAAAUGAAUAUUGGUGAGGAUGUGGAGAAAUUGAAUGUCUUGUCCAUUGCUGGAAAAUGGUGCAACUGCUGUGGAAGCACUUUAACAGUUCCUGAAAAAGGUAAACAUAGAAUUACGUUAUGAUCCAGCAAUUCCACUCCUAGGUAUAGACUCGAGGAAAUUAAAAGCAGAGACUUGAGGAGAUACUUGUAUGCCAAUAUCCAUUGCAGCAUUAUUCACAGUAGCCAGAAAUGGGAAACAACCCAAGGGCCUAUCAGCAGAUGAAUGAGUAAACAAAAUGUGGUAUAUACAAACAACGGGAUAUUAUUUGGCCAUAGGAAAGGAAUCAGGAUCUGAAACAUGCUGAUAUGGAUGAAUCUUGGAAAUAUUAUGUGAAGUGAAAUAAGCCAGACACAAAAGGACAAAUAUUGUAUGACUCCACUUAUAUGAAAUAUCUAGAAUAGGCAAAUUCAUACAGACAGGAAGCAAAUCAGAGAUUACCAGAGGGCACCCAGGUGUGGUGGCUCACACUUUAAUCCCAGCACUUUGGGAGGCAUAGGUGCAAGGAUGGCUUGAGGCCAAGGCCCGGAGUUCCAGACCAGUCAGGGCAAACACAGGGCAAAUGCAAAACAAAAGCCCUUCCCUACAAAAAAUAUUUUUUAAGUUAGCUGGAUGUGGCGGCUCAUGCCUGUAGUCCCAGCUAUUCAGGAGGCUGAGGCAGAGGAUUGCCUGAGCCCAGGAGGUGGAGGCUACAGUGAGAUUUGAUUGGCCCUCUGCACUUCAGCCUGAGUGAUAGUGCAAGACCUUGUCUUUAAAAAAAAGAAAGAGAGAGAGAGAGAUUACCAGGUGCUGGAGGGAGGAAGAAUGGGGAAUUAUCGUAUAAUGUUUACAGAAUUUCUGUUUCGAAUAACAAAAAUGUUCCAGAACAAAAAUGUUCCAGAUAUUGUGCAUAAGAAAUGAUGCACAACAAUGUGAAUAUUUUAUGUUAUGUAUGUUUUGCCAUAAUUUAAAAAAAUUAAUAAUGUAAUAUACCAAAAGUUAUUGCAUGAAUUGUGCACUUUGAAUUGUAUACUUGAAUUGUACACUUUAAAUGUAUGAAUUGUGUGAUAUGUGAAUUAUAUCUCAAUAAAGUUGUUCUAAAAAAUGCCA